GCUGUAGCUAAGAUCAGUCCACUGCAGCAGGAGUUUCAAGAACAGCAGCACAAAAAUAAUGACUUAACUGGAUAGAAAAAAAGGCACAUAUUUUCAGGAAGGCCUCUUUAUUCUUAGAAGUUACCCUUCAAGAUGACAAGUGGUGCAAACUCUUCAGGAUCUUACCUGCCCUCAGAAAUAAGAAGUUCUAAAAUAGAUGACAACUACUUGAAGGAAUUGAAUGAGGACUUAAAGCUAAGGAAGCAGGAACUGCUAGAGAUGCUCAAACCUCUAGAAGAUAAAAACAACCUCUUAUUUCAAAAGUUAAUGUCUAACUUGGAGGAAAAACAAAGGAGUCUUCAGAUCAUGAGACAGAUCAUGGCAGGGAAGGGGUGUGAGGAAUCCUCGGUCAUGGAGCUCCUUAAGGAAGCAGAGGAGAUGAAACAGAACUUGGAAAGGAAAAACAAGAUGCUUCGGAAGGAAAUGGAGAUGCUAUGGAACAAGACAUUCGAGGCAGAAGAACUUAGUGAUCAACAAAAAGCACCACAGACAAAAAACAAGGCAGACUUGCAGGAUGGAAAGGCUCCCAAAUCCCCCUCAUCACCUAGGAAGACUGAGAGUGAACUGGAGAAAUCAUUUGCAGAGAAAGUGAAGGAGAUAAGGAAGGAAAAGCAACAGAGGAAAAUGGAAUGGGUCAAGUAUCAGGAACAAAAUAACAUCCUUCAGAAUGAUUUUCAUGGCAAAGUGAUUGAGCUGAGAAUUGAAGCCUUGAAGAACUACCAGAAGGCCAAUGACCUGAAAUUAUCACUGUAUUUGCAGCAGAAUUUUGAGCCAAUGCAAGCAUUUUUAAAUCUUCCUGGGUCCCAAGGAAUUAGAAUUGUUUAAUCUUAUUAAUCUUGCUGGAAUAGACUCUGCUACUUCAAAGCAGAAGGCCAAGGAGACAGACAUCUGACAAAGCCCAGUAGGUGGCACCAACCACAUCCAGGCUUCAAGUCCACAGAGUGGUAAUUCAGGAACCAUGAAAUGCUGUGGGAGAGAUCGGUCUUCUAUUACUCUCAGGACAAAAGCAUUUCCUUGAGCUCUUCUGAGAAAAACCUGAACGUUGGAUGUACUAUGGGCAUUACAACUAUGGACAGAGUGACUACUGGCAGAAAUGAACACCAUGUGAGAAUUCUGGGAACAAAGAUCUACACAGAACAACAAGGAACUAAAGGAAGUCAGCUUGAUAAUACAGGAGGGAGACUCUUUUUUCUGAGGUCAUUGCCAGAUGAAGCACUGAAGAAUUAGCAGGCUUUCGCUCCAUUUGCUUUGGACAGAUUUAAAGACUAGGCACAGCCAUUUGUGUUAAUUAAAAUCUCUCGCACCUUU